GUUUUCCGGUCACACUGAGGAGACAGGUCUGGGAGCAGGAAGAUGCGGGCAUUCAUUCCCGGAGGAGGAGCAGGGCGCCAGCCCUGGCCGGGCUGGACGGGGUAACAGCAGGCACACCCCCGGCCCUGUCUGAGGCCCGCACCACCCUAGCCCACGGCCAGGCCUGGGUAGAUCCAGGUGGUGAGUAGGGGAGGCCCGCCACGUGGCCGGCGAGGUCAGCAGGGGUUCAUGGGAAAGGACUUGUCGGCCACAGGAGAGGACAUCCUGCCUGCAUUUCCCUCUUCCUGCGGCAGGAGCUGGUGGCCCCGAUUUAGCAGCACUGGGGGGCCACCUCUGCGCCAGCUGGGUUGUCUGAUAACGCCGCUCGUCCUGCCGGCCAGCAAGCAGAGCCUUGACCCCACGGAAGCCGGGGAAACUGCCUGGCAUAGCUGGCUGCCCCACGGCGGCCGUGUGCUGGGAGCUUAGCAUCUGCUCAGGCCCCCUCCUCCUGGUCUCCACCCCCACGGGGCACUCAGGCAGCCCACGCUCCCCGCAGGUCCAGCCCUUCUCAACCUCAUCACCACUCCCUGUUUCCAGCAUCUUCCAGAAAUUUGUCUCCAUUCUGCCCCAAAGGGACUGCUGUAAAUGAGCCUUCAGGGCCCCCCCCAACUCACCCACAAGAUAAGCACCAGCUUCUUGGGCUCGUGGUACCGGCCCUUCCUGCUGGAGUCCCAGGCCAUCCCUAGCCCCGCGUCCACCCAGCCUCCACCCACUGCACACACCAGCCCCAGCACCAUGGCCUUUCGCCCACCCUGGACGUGCCCUUUGGGAGACUGCUGGGAACUCCGGGCAGACGGUGCUGCUCCAAGCGGAAGGGGCCUUCCGGGGCAGGUGAUGGCUUCGUUCCCGCUCACAGUGUGCCUCAGACUUUCAGGCCUGGUGAGUGGCUACUCCAUGACCCCCCCGACCUUGAACAUCACGGAGGAGUCACACGUCAUCGACACCGGUGACAGCCUGUCCAUCUCCUGCAGGGGACAGCACCCCCUCGAGUGGGCUUGGCCAGGAGCUCAGGAGGCGCCAGCCACCGGAGACAAGGACAGCGAGGACACGGGGGUGGUGCGAGACUGCGAGGGCACAGACGCCAGGCCCUACUGCAAGGUGUUGCUGCUGCACGAGGUACAUGCCAACGACACAGGCAGCUACGUCUGCUACUACAAGUACAUCAAGGCACGCAUCGAGGGCACCACGGCCGCCAGCUCCUACGUGUUCGUGAGAGACUUUGAGCAGCCAUUCAUCAACAAGCCUGACACGCUCUUGGUCAACAGGAAGGACGCCAUGUGGGUGCCCUGUCUGGUGUCCAUCCCCGGCCUCAAUGUCACGCUGCGCUCGCAAAGCUCGGUGCUGUGGCCAGACGGGCAGGAGGUGGUGUGGGAUGACCGGCGGGGCAUGCUCGUGUCCACGCCACUGCUGCACGAUGCCCUGUACCUGCAGUGCGAGACCACCUGGGGAGACCAGGACUUCCUUUCCAACCCCUUCCUGGUGCACAUCACAGGCAACGAGCUCUAUGACAUCCAGCUGUUGCCCAGGAAGUCGCUGGAGCUGCUGGUAGGGGAGAAGCUGGUCCUGAACUGCACCGUGUGGGCUGAGUUUAACUCAGGUGUCACCUUUGACUGGGACUACCCAGGGAAGCAGGCAGAGCGGGGUAAGUGGGUGCCCGAGCGACGCUCCCAGCAGACCCACACAGAACUCUCCAGCAUCCUGACCAUCCACAACGUCAGCCAGCACGACCUGGGCUCGUAUGUGUGCAAGGCCAACAACGGCAUCCAGCGAUUUCGGGAGAGCACCGAGGUCAUUGUGCAUGAAAAUCCCUUCAUCAGCGUCGAGUGGCUCAAAGGACCCAUCCUGGAGGCCACGGCAGGAGACGAGCUGGUGAAGCUGCCCGUGAAGCUGGCAGCGUACCCCCCGCCCGAGUUCCAGUGGUACAAGGAUGGAAAGGCACUGUCCGGGCGCCACAGUCCACAUGCCCUGGUGCUCAAGGAGGUGACAGAGGCCAGCACAGGCACCUACACCCUCGCCCUGUGGAACUCCGCUGCUGGCCUGAGGCGCAACAUCAGCCUGGAGCUGGUGGUGAAUGUGCCCCCCCAGAUACAUGAGAAGGAGGCCUCCUCCCCCAGCAUCUACUCGCGUCACAGCCGCCAGGCCCUCACCUGCACGGCCUACGGGGUGCCCCUGCCUCUCAGCAUCCAGUGGCACUGGCGGCCCUGGACACCCUGCAAGAUGUUUGCCCAGCGUAGUCUCCGGCGGCGGCAGCAGCAAGACCUCAUGCCACAGUGCCGUGACUGGAGGGCGGUGACCACGCAGGAUGCCGUGAACCCCAUCGAGAGCCUGGACACCUGGACCGAGUUUGUGGAGGGAAAGAAUAAGACUGUGAGCAAGCUGGUGAUCCAGAAUGCCAACGUGUCUGCCAUGUACAAGUGUGUGGUCUCCAACAAGGUGGGCCAGGAUGAGCGGCUCAUCUACUUCUAUGUGACCACCAUCCCCGACGGCUUCACCAUCGAAUCCAAGCCAUCCGAGGAGCUACUAGAGGGCCAGCCGGUGCUCCUGAGCUGCCAAGCCGACAGCUACAAGUACGAGCAUCUGCGCUGGUACCGCCUCAACCUGUCCACGCUGCACGAUGCGCACGGGAACCCGCUUCUGCUCGACUGCAAGAACGUGCAUCUGUUCGCCACCCCUCUGGCCGCCAGCCUGGAGGAGGUGGCACCUGGGGCGCGCCACGCCACGCUCAGCCUGAGUAUCCCCCGCGUCGCGCCCGAGCACGAGGGCCACUAUGUGUGCGAAGUGCAAGACCGGCGCAGCCAUGACAAGCACUGCCACAAGAAGUACCUGUCGGUGCAGGCCCUGGAAGCCCCUCGGCUCACGCAGAACUUGACCGACCUCCUGGUGAACGUGAGCGACUCGCUGGAGAUGCAGUGCUUGGUGGCCGGAGCGCACGCGCCCAGCAUCGUGUGGUACAAAGACGAGAGGCUGCUGGAGGAAAAGUCUGGAGUCGACUUGGCGGACUCCAACCAGAAGCUGAGCAUCCAGCGCGUGCGCGAGGAGGAUGCGGGACGCUAUCUGUGCAGCGUGUGCAACGCCAAGGGCUGCGUCAACUCCUCCGCCAGCGUGGCCGUGGAAGGCUCCGAGGAUAAGGGCAGCAUGGAGAUCGUGAUCCUUGUCGGUACCGGCGUCAUCGCUGUCUUCUUCUGGGUCCUCCUCCUCCUCAUCUUCUGUAACAUGAGGAGGCCGGCCCACGCAGACAUCAAGACGGGCUACCUGUCCAUCAUCAUGGACCCCGGGGAGGUGCCUCUGGAGGAGCAAUGCGAAUACCUGUCCUACGAUGCCAGCCAGUGGGAAUUCCCCCGAGAGCGGCUGCACCUGGGGAGAGUGCUCGGCUACGGCGCCUUCGGGAAGGUGGUGGAAGCCUCCGCUUUCGGCAUCCACAAGGGCAGCAGCUGUGACACCGUGGCCGUGAAAAUGCUGAAAGAGGGCGCCACGGCCAGCGAGCACCGCGCGCUGAUGUCGGAGCUCAAGAUCCUCAUUCACAUCGGCAACCACCUCAACGUGGUCAACCUCCUCGGGGCGUGCACCAAGCCGCAGGGCCCCCUCAUGGUGAUCGUGGAGUUCUGCAAGUACGGCAACCUCUCCAACUUCCUGCGCGCCAAGCGGGACGCCUUCAGCCCCUGCGCGGAGAAGUCUCCCGAGCAGCGCGGACGCUUCCGCGCCAUGGUGGAGCUCGCCAGGCUGGAUCGGAGGCGGCCGGGGAGCAGCGACAGGGUCCUCUUCGCGCGGUUCUCGAAGACCGAGGGCGGAGCGAGGCGGGCUUCUCCAGACCAAGAAGCUGAGGACCUGUGGCUGAGCCCGCUGACCAUGGAAGAUCUUGUCUGCUACAGCUUCCAGGUGGCCAGAGGGAUGGAGUUCCUGGCUUCCCGAAAGUGCAUCCACAGAGACCUGGCUGCUCGGAACAUUCUGCUGUCGGAAAGCGACGUGGUGAAGAUCUGUGACUUUGGCCUUGCCCGGGACAUCUACAAAGACCCCGACUACGUCCGCAAGGGCAGUGCCCGGCUGCCCCUGAAGUGGAUGGCCCCUGAAAGCAUCUUCGACAAGGUGUACACCACGCAGAGUGACGUGUGGUCCUUUGGGGUGCUUCUCUGGGAGAUCUUCUCUCUGGGGGCCUCCCCGUACCCUGGGGUGCAGAUCAAUGAGGAGUUCUGCCAGCGGCUGAGAGACGGCACAAGGAUGAGGGCCCCGGAGCUGGCCACUCCCGCCAUACGCCGCAUCAUGCUGAACUGCUGGUCCGGAGACCCCAAGGCGAGACCUGCAUUCUCGGAGCUGGUGGAGAUCCUGGGGGACCUGCUCCAGGGCAGGGGCCUGCAAGAGGAAGAGGAGGUCUGCAUGGCCCCGCGCAGCUCUCAGAGCUCAGAAGAGGGCAGCUUCUCGCAGGUGUCCACCAUGGCCCUACACAUCGCCCAGGCUGACGCUGAGGACAGCCCGCCAAGCCUGCAGCGCCACAGCCUGGCCGCCAGGUAUUACAACUGGGUGUCCUUUCCCGGGUGCCUGGCCAGAGGGGCUGAGACCCGUGGUUCCUCCAGGAUGAAGACAUUUGAGGAAUUCCCCAUGACCCCAACGACCUACAAAGGCUCUGUGGGGCAUGUGACCCUCACCCUGGGAUGGAAUGGACGCCUUGUUUCUGGCUCAGCUUCCCAGGGACAGGUGUUAGGACAACCAGACAGACAGUGGGAUGGUGCUGGCCUCGGAGGAGUUUGAGCAGAUAGAGAGCAGGCAUAGACAAGAAAGCGGCUUCAGCUGUAAAGGACCUGGCCAGAAUGUGGCUGUGACCAGGGCACACCCUGACUCCCAAGGGAGGCGGCGGCGGCCUGAGCGGGGGGCCCGAGGAGGCCAGGUGUUUUACAACAGCGAGUAUGGGGAGCUGUCGGAGCCAAGCGAGGAGGACCACUGCUCCCCGUCUGCCCGCGUGACUUUCUUCACAGACAACAGCUACUAAGCAGCAUCGGACAAGACCCCCAGCACUUGGGGGUUCAGGCCCGGCAGGGCGGGCAGAGGGCUGGAGGCCCAGGCUGGGAACUCAUCUGGUUGAACUCUGGUGGCACAGGAGUGUCCUCUUCCCUCUCUGCAGACUUCCCAGCUAGGAAGAGCAGGACUCCAGGCCCAAGGCUCCCGGAAUUCCGUCACCACGACUGGCCAGGGCCACGCUCCAGCUGCCCCGGCCCCUCCCCCUGAGAUUCAGAUGUCAUUUAGUUCAGCAUCCGCAGGUGCUGGUCCCGGGGCCAGCACUUCCAUGGGAAUGUCUCUUUGGCGACCUCCUUUCAUCACACUGGGUGGUGGCCUGGUCCCUGUUUUCCCACGAGGAAUCUGUGGGUCUGGGAGUCACACAGUGUUGGAGGUUAAGGCAUACGAGAGCAGAGGUCUCCCAAACGCCCUUUCCUCCUCAGGCACACAGCUACUCUCCCCACGAGGGCUGGCUGGCCUCACCCACCCCUGCACAGUUGAAGGGAGGGGCUGUGUUUCCAUCUCAAAGAAGGCAUUUGCAGGGUCCUCUUCUGGGCCUGACCAAACAGCCAACUAGCCCCUGGGGUGGCCACCAGUAUGACAGUAUUAUACGCUGGCAACACAGAGGCAGCCCGCACACCUGCGCCUGGGUGUUGAGAGCCAUCCUGCAAGUCUUUUUCAACAGAACUUCACAGACUGUUAGAGCUGCUGAGAAGAAUUUGCUUUCCGAAUUCAGCCUGGAAGGCGCCCAGGGACAGCUGUACUGAGUCUAGAUGACUCUGACCCCCGCCCCAGGUCAAGGCCAGCAGAGCAGUCAGUGCCUCUGGAGAAGGCCCUUGCUCUCCCACCUGGCCCAGACUCCGAGGAGCCUGGGUCUGGAGCUGCCGGUCUGGUUCUUCCCUUUAGAGCCCGGAUCUGCCACCUGCGGCCCCUCCCAAGCCGUGAACCAGCUCAUGAGAGAUGAACACUGUGGGAUCCACUCAGGAAGGCUCGGGGCUGGCACAAAGGACCACCCAGCAUUGCCCUGUGCCACCCAGCACUCAGUGGACAUUCUGGGGACCUGCCUUCAGCCUUUUCCUGCCCUGUGCCUGACAUCAGCACCCUGGCUGGUCAGAAUGCCGCCCUCCCAGAGGAGCAGCCGAGAGAUCCCCUGAAGGCUGGAGGCAUUCUGCUCAGGACCCCUAUCCCAGCUCACAGUGCCCAACCAUCUCACCAGGAGAAAGAGCCACAUCCCCACGUUAGGACCACGGAGACUGACCACCACCCUGACCCCCCAAACCCACGCACCAGACGCUUGCAGGACAGGCGCCGCGCAGCGGGCAGGGGCUUGCCCGGCCGACCCUCCCCUCCCCACCUCCCCCACUGCGCGUUACUCCAGGAUAUGCCGAGUGCACGUAUAAGGUCAUCUUCGUCGUCCCCGUGGACCUCCCCCUUCCUCUGCACGUCGUCCAACGUGGGACUGGCGUGUCAGGCUUCCCUGGGAGGAUCUGGAGGUUGUUCUCUGCAGAGAACCAGCCUGGCUCCUGGCGCGCACCUCUGCUCCCUUCUCCUCACUACCCACCCACGCAUGUACCGGGAAAAAAACUACUAUGCCCUUCUAGACCAUGUUCUGAGAAAAGAUCGAAAAUAUUUAACAAGAGAUAAUAAUAAAUCUGAUGCCGGUCUUUGUGUGUGUUGCGGA